GUUUCUGCCAAACCUUUAAUGGUGAUUUGCUAUGCUAUACGGUGAUUCUGCUUUUAAAACAAAAUUGCAUCUUUGAAGGCCACUGCUUCCUGUGUAAUGGAAAAAGGGGAUUUAUAAACAUCAUUUGUUUGAAGAACUUGGUACAUAUUAGGUUCUAUAAUACACCGGGCUAAGAGUAUUCUUUCUUUAAAUCUGUUCUAAGCAAAUUUAGCCACCGAUGUUUCCAGUUUACAGUACUUGGAGAUUGCAUUCAGUUUGAGUAGAGCACAUCCUUUGUCCUGUCAUUGCUUAUAUUGAUCCCCAAUUCAUCUGCAUGACUUGCACGCUUUCUCAGCAUGGUCUCUAGUUCUUUUCCACAAGGUGAUUUAGGUGACAUCAUAAAAUGAGAGGGCUUCAGACAGACCUGUGUUCCUCACAUUUACAUACCUGCAUUGUCUGCUCCUCUCCUCUCUUCAGACAUAUUGAUACAUAGGCUUUUGGCUAUUUUCAUUUUCUUCAAAACAGUAAAGAACUAAAGGCAACUUUGGCGAUUAAAGCCUUGAUUUGGUUGAAUGAGAAUUUUUACUUUGAUGUUCCUGUAUUUGCAUAUAUUUAUUAUUUAUCUUCAUUAAUGUGUUUCUAUUAGUUUGAUUACUUAAAGAUUUAAUGGACAUGUGUGUAAUGGAUCCCAAAGAAUCAAAUAGUAUUUUAAACUACUACUAUUUAAGUAGAAACUAGUAUAAAACUGUAAAUACUACUAUAAGACAUUGGCUUUUUCCAGACAUGGAUCCAAAAAAUUUCUGCAUCUACUUUGAAAGUUUGUUAUGUAUGGUUGUAUUUACUUUUGUUUUAUCUUCUUUUGGGGGUUGGGUGAUUUGUUCUAGAUGUCUCCUGGAGUAUGAAGUCAUCUGAAGGUAUAAGUAUUUAACUGUGGUUCUCUGAAGUUUCCUGGCAUGCUGUGAAGCACUGCUGACAGCUUGGGUUUCUUAUCUUUUCACGAGGAGGUUCUUGUUUCUGUUAACUUAGCUGACCUUAAAGUGUAGACUUUAGGUCCGUGUUGCAGUUGGUAUUAGGAAUUUUGACUUCCAGAACCUGCUUUUUAAGAGACAGAAAAACAUCAUUUCUAAAUUUAUUUGUGUCUUUGCGGUAAGGAUUAUUUUUCGUGUUCAUGAACUGUCUGCACAAUAUUCUGAUUAAAGUGCUUUCUGUGGGCAUUAUUUUGUUGUAUCUGUGAAUGAAGUUGUUAGAGUAAUGGUUGGUAGAUCUGUUGAUAAUCAGUAGGGGAACUGCUUUGGAAUUUUAAGUGGAAGCAGUAUUUUACACUUUUUUUUUUUAAGAGACAGAGUCUCAUUCUGUCGCCCAGGCUGGAGUGUAGUGACAUGAUCUUGGCUCACUACAACCUCUGCCUCCCGGGUUCAAGUGAUUCUCCCACCUAAAUUCCCAAGUAUCUGGGAUUAAGGGCGCCUGCCACCAUGCCUGGCUUUUUUGUAUUUUUAGUGAGACGGGGUUUCACCACGUUGUCCAGGCUGGUCUCGAACUCCUGACCUCAGGUAAUCCAUCCGCCUCGGCCUCCUAAAGUUACACGGUUUUAAUACUUGAAAAAAUAUUUAUGUUUUGUAAACAUGUUGUUAUGUUUAAAUAUGAAAUUAAAAACAAUUUAAAUCCUCUGAUUAUUAAGCCAGGGAACUGCAAACAUUAAAUUUUCUGCCUGCAAUUAAGAGAUAGUAAUUAUUGUUUUAAACACUAAUCCAAUUUUUAAAAAUCUAUGCUUGUAAUACAGGCAGUUUCCAACUUGACAAAUGUUUUAUGGUCUAUAUGAGCAACCAGUAGAAAAGUACAAGUCUCUAGGGCAUAAUUAUUUCUCUUUAUUCUUAGAAUGAGGUGGUUCAAAACCUCCAACUGUUAACCUUUUAAUAGCUUUCAGUCACCUGGAAAGGUGAUUGCUUCAGAGAUGUUCUUUUCUCUGUUUUCAAAUAUAAGAAGUUACCUAGUUAGUGUUGCCAGAAAUAAACUUCUCCCUUUCAUGCAGCUAGGGAGGAGAUGUUAAAACAUGGGAUUCAUUUUUCCCCAGAGAAAUAAUUUAUAAAGGUGGGUAGGUUUGGUUGAAGCAGUGUGUUAAUAUUUUACCUAAAAUACAUUGUAGAUUAAUAUUUUUAGACUUUUUCGGUAAUCUGAGAAAACUAUUAUGUGUGACUUUUUUUAACUUGGGAAAAUACGUUCUAAGCAUACUUUUUGGAGUAAAACCUGUUCGAAAGUUGGAGACUGCCUGUACCCAGGUUGAUAGUCAAUUGUUUUUAAUGCUAGUAAAUCUUAACACUAAUACAAGUAAAAAUAUUUGUGUGGAAAACUAAUCCUUUCUUUAUUCGUGCAUUUUUAACUUUAUAGGUAUUAAAACUUUCUUUGUAUGAUCAUAAUUUUUUGAUCUUUUUGUUUUGCAAGAAAGUGAAUGGUAGCCUUUCAUUUGUAUGUUUGAUUUUCUUAAAAAUUUCAUAUUUAUUAUGUUAUUUUACAAAUGAAAAAUUAUUUGUGAGAAAUGUUUUGUCAAUCAUUGUGCAUUAGUUUUUAGUUAUAAACACUUAAGGAAAGAAAAUGAUUAUUCCCGGCUUACAGAUAAGAAAACUGAACAAAGGACAGAGAUAUAUAUAACUUGCUGAAAAGCAUAAGCACCUCCUCAGAGUUCAUUUUAUAUGACUUCUCAUUUCCUAGUUAGACUCAUGGUAUCUAUAUUAAAAUAACUCCCAAGAAAAACCUUACUGUUUGGAAUGGUGAUCGGUAUGCAGUUAGAUACUCUCCUGAGAGGCAAAAUUGGCUUUGUCAGCCUGUUAAUAUUACCAGUGAAGGCUGUUGGAACAGCUUUACCAGCACCUUCUGCUAGAGCAGAACAUUUGUAAAGUUUCACUGAGUGUAUAAUUUUGUUAAUUAUAAAUCCUUUUUUUUUGAGAUGGAGUUUUGCUCUUGUUGCCCAGGCUGGAGUGCAAUGGCGCGAUCUUGGCUCACCGCAACCUCCGCCUCCCAGGUUCAAGCAAUUCUCCUGCCUCAGCCUCCCGAGUAGCUGGGAUUACAGGCAUGCACCACCACGCCCGGCUAAUUUUGUAUUUUUAGUAGAGACAGGGUUUCUCCAUGUUGAGGCUGGUCUCGAACUCCUGACCUCAGGUGAUCUGCCUGCCUCAGCCUCCCAAAGUGCUGGGAUUAUAGGCGUGAGCCACCGUGCCUGGCUAAUUAUAAAUUCUUUUAAAGGUACUGAUUAAAAUAGUUAAAUGGUAGUAGGUUAAUAAUUUAAAUUUGUUCAGCAGCUCUCAUUUUUGCAUUUAUAACUUCUUGAAAAAUGAGGAAGUGCAUUUGAUUUGUUGUAGAUAUAAAUACUGGUUUAAGAUCAGGAAUUCUAUUUUUCUUUCCUCUGAGAAAGGUGUUCUUUGAUGUACAUCUCUUGCAACUCUGAUACUUGGAAGUUGGAUUUUAGAAGCUAUUUGAAACAUUAAAAAUAUUAAAAUAAUGAUGUGUUCAGAGCAACAUUGUUUUGUUGACACAAGCAUUUAGAAGAAAGUUUGUGAUUCCUGACUUUAUGUCUUUUACCUCACACAUUGAUGAGUUAUAUGAAAGUGCUAAAAAGCAGUCUGGAGGAAAGGUUGCAGAUUAUAUUCCUCAACUGGCCAAAUUCAGUCCCGAUUUGUGGGGUGUGUCUGUUUGUACAGUAGAUGGACAGAGGCAUUCUACUGGAGAUACCAAAGUUCCCUUCUGUCUUCAGUCCUGUGUAAAACCUUUGAAAUAUGCCAUUGCUGUUAAUGAUCUUGGAACUGAAUAUGUGCAUCGAUAUGUUGGAAAAGAGCCGAGUGGACUAAGAUUCAACAAACUAUUUUUGAAUGAAGAUGAUAAACCACAUAAUCCUAUGGUAAAUGCUGGAGCAAUUGUUGUGACUUCACUAAUAAAGCAAGGAGUAAAUAAUGCUGAAAAAUUUGACUAUGUCAUGCAGUUUUUGAAUAAGAUGGCUGGUAAUGAAUAUGUUGGAUUCAGUAAUGCAACGUUUCAGUCUGAAAGAGAAAGUGGAGAUCGAAAUUUUGCAAUAGGAUAUUACUUAAAAGAAAAGAAGUGUUUUCCAGAAGGCACAGACAUGGUUGGUAUAUUAGACUUCUACUUCCAGCUGUGCUCCAUUGAAGUGACUUGUGAAUCAGCCAGUGUGAUGGCUGCGACACUGGCUAAUGGUGGUUUCUGCCCAAUUACUGGUGAAAGAGUACUGAGCCCUGAAGCAGUUCGAAAUACAUUGAGUUUGAUGCAUUCCUGUGGCAUGUAUGACUUCUCAGGGCAGUUUGCUUUCCAUGUUGGUCUUCCUGCAAAAUCUGGAGUUGCUGGGGGCAUUCUUUUAGUUGUCCCCAAUGUUAUGGGUAUGAUGUGCUGGUCUCCUCCUCUGGAUAAGAUGGGCAACAGUGUUAAGGGAAUUCACUUUUGUCACGAUCUUGUUUCUCUGUGUAAUUUCCAUAACUAUGAUAAUUUGAGACACUUUGCAAAAAAACUUGAUCCUCGAAGAGAAGGUGGUGAUCAAAGGGUAAAGUCAGUGAUAAAUCUUUUGUUUGCUGCAUAUACUGGAGAUGUGUCUGCACUUCGAAGAUUUGCUUUGUCAGCUAUGGACAUGGAACAGCGGGACUAUGAUUCUAGAACAGCACUCCAUGUAGCUGCUGCAGAGGGUCAUGUUGAAGUUGUUAAAUUUUUGCUGGAAGCCUGCAAAGUAAACCCUUUCCCCAAGGACAGGUGGAAUAACACUCCCAUGGAUGAAGCACUGCACUUUGGACACCAUGAUGUAUUUAAAAUUCUCCAAGAAUACCAAGUCCAGUACACACCUCAAGGAGAUUCUGACAACGGGAAGGAAAAUCAAACCGUCCAUAAGAAUCUUGAUGGAUUGUUGUAAUGGUCUCAAAUCCCAAGAUUUAAAUCACUUACCUAUUUAAUUGUGGAAAAUGAUUAUGAAGAACAUGUGUAUUUCUAUCUGGUAGUGAUGUAUAUUUUACAUUUGUCAUUUCAGUGUUACUGGAGUUUUCUUCAUUGUGCACACAGGACAAAUCUGAUCUCUUUGGGAAAAAAUAGAAAUAAAACAAUCUCCCUCCAUAAUGUGAGCAAUAUUACCUCGUGCAUUGUAUAAUUUGAUGUAAAAGAAAUAGUUACCAAUGCUAGCUUGUGUGGUCUUCCAUGAUUUAUUUGUGUUUUGUGAAUUUUCAAUUUAUGGUGAUGAUCUGCUGAUAUGCAUUUAUAAAGUAAGCUCUGUUGUACAGUCUGUCCAAAUGGGUCAAGGUUGCCUUUAGAAGCAAAUAGUGUGAUUUUCAAGACUUCAAAUACAAAUUUAGUUUAAGUGUUUGAACAACUAUAUGCACUUACGGUUGUGUGUUUAAAAUGUCUCUCUCACCCCCUAGCUUCAUGAUGUGACUCUUAAAAAACUAUAAUAGUUAACAACUGUUAGUAAGAUAGACCAAUUCUGAUUAGACUUUAUCAGGGAAUCUGUUUAAGAUAUGUUUGGUGACCAAAACGUAUGUGUGAAUGUAGUUAUAAUGCUUUUGAAAAAUUUUCCUUUUUCUAUAUCCCCUUAGUCCAGCCUCUCUUCUCAGACAUUUAGCUAUCUGCCUCUUUCCUUUAGCUGGGAAAGUGAGAGCUGGCAUACUAUGCAGUUUUUAUGUUUUCCAUAGUAAGUCAGAAAAUGCCUCCUAUUUCUGGCAUCAGAACUUUGCCAUUUGUCUACAGAAGACGAACCAGAGACAAAAUUACUAAGUAUAAAUUAGUCAAGUUUAUCAGUCUAAAAAACGAAGGGAUGUGCAACUGCAGCUCUUUAAGAAGUUUUUUUUUUUUAGCUUCUAGGGUAAAGAUAAAUUCAGAAAUGCUCUAAGCUACCAAAGUUAUUCUGAAAGUAUGGGAACUGCUACAACUAACAAACAUUUGUUUCCAAGCCUGUCAUUAAGAGUCUGCAUCAAGAGAUUUGUCCUCCUUGGGGGACCACUGGAUCAUUCCAGAUUUCUUGUGAUUUUUCUAUUGUGUAAUUCUUGGUGGGCUCUGUAGUUUAAUAAUAAGAAAAAGGCCAUUUCAUUUUAAAUUGUGACCUAUAAUUCUUUGUCUUGGGUUGGUAAUUCAGGAUUCAUUUGGAAAGUGGGUAAAAGGGGCUUCAAAAAACGGAUAGAACAGGAUUUUCUAGGAGUUACACAUACAUUUUAUCCUGUCAUACCUCGAGAUAAAGUGGCAUGUUAGUGAGGAGUUCUGAUAUUAAGCACACACACACAUGCACACAAAUGGACUUCUCUGAAGCUGUGUUUAGUGAAAUGAGCUCAAGUACAUGAAUGUUAGUUGUUAUCACAUACAGCAAAUUCCUUUUUUUUUCUUUUUCUAUGAGCACACUCUGCUGCUUCUAAACUUUACAUGCCUGAUGGCACCUUACUCCAGCAGCCUCCAGGUGCUUUCAUUUUCACUUCCAGUCUAAGCCAGUGGCUCCUGCCACUGCCCUCCCAUUACCUAGAUGGCACCUCCUUUGGUGAAACCACGGCCAAUGUUCCUUAGCUGCACCAGGCCCGAAGCUGUUCCCAUGCUUGAGCUUCCAUGGGGAGGAUGCUGAGUGAGCAGUUUCCUACCCCGUGGAUCUAGCAAGCCAUGGAGACAGGUAGCAUUUGUAAGAUGCUGCACAGGAGCAGCAUUAUCCCCAAAGAUAUUACAGGGUAGACACGUUUUAACUGAAAUCAAUCAAGAUAACUUUAUUCAAAGAGCAGCCCGCUUUGUGUGACUAAAAUGAAACAAGACAGUUGAAUUGUGUGACUUGAAGAUUACCAAUGAUUUUGAGGCUUUUCUAUAAUAAAAAGAGGUUCUAACCAUUAUUUGGGAACAAAGAGAGUUUUCAUCUUUUUUCAGAUCAAAACCAUUCUGUAAAAUCUUUGUUGUUUAAUUAAAUGUGCCGUUAUUUACCCCUGAUGUUAUUUAUGACUAUGUGCCGAUUCCUGCUCGGGCUGUUUGCUGUUGGCUGGUAAUAAUAUAUUUGAUUUAAAUGCUGUUGACUGUGCUAUUAACUGCUGCCGUCAGUAAACUCCAAAGAUCUUUUUGUUUUGGCUUUAGUAUCAUAUGUGCUUUUUCUGUAUCCUGAGCGCUCUAUAUGAUCAUGUUAAUUUAAAGCUUUAUACACAUUGUUGUUUUUGCUGGUCUCAUCUUUGGUAAUAUGCUAUACCCCACUGCUGCCCGACACUGCCCUUUAGCUGCAGAGCUGGAUUAGCUGUUGACCAUUUGAUGCUGUUGUCUGUCUGGCAGGGACUGAAUGACCUGAUGUCAGAUUUAGAUUCUUCCUGGGGAUUACACAGCUAUGAAUGUAUUUGCUUCUAAAACCUCCCAAAGUGAAUCUAAUCUUAAAACUACAAGUUGUAAGUAUUCUGAAAUUGGGAAACAUUUAUUUUAAAUGCAAUCAGGUAGUGUUGCUUUUUACAGCAUAAUAAAUAUAUGUAUCAAAAAAAAAA